GAAUGCCCUGGAGUUGUGAGGGUGUGAGGGUCGCGUUCCUGCUGUCUGGACUUUUUCUGUCCCACUGAGACGCAGCUGGUAGGUCCGCAGGCCAGUCCUCCCAAGGGUUGAAGUGUGAGUGCGUGUGAGGAGGAGCCAGUGGCUGUCCGGAGCGUGGGAAAGCAUAGCCCGUGGCCUCAGAGGCCGAAGGGUCUCAAGUGUGAAAUAUGAUUUGGCGAGGAAGAUCAACAUAUAGGCCUAGGCCGAGGAGAAGUGUACCACCUCCUGAGCUGAUUGGGCCUAUGCUGGAGCCCGGUGAUGAGGAGCCUCAGCAAGAGGAACCACCAACUGAAAGUCGGGAUCCUGCACCUGGUCAGGAGAGAGAAGAAGAUCAGGGUGCAGCUGAGACUCAAGUGCCUGACCUGGAAGCUGAUCUCCAGGAGCUGUCUCAGUCAAAGACUGGGGGUGAAUGUGGAAAUGGUCCUGAUGACCAGGGGAAGAUUCUGCCAAAAUCAGAACAAUUUAAAAUGCCAGAAGGAGGUGACAGGCAACCACAGGUUUAAAUGAAGACAAGCUGAAACAACACAAAACUGUUUUUAUCUAAGAUAUUUGACUUAAAAAUAUCGAAAUAAACUUUUGCAGCUUUCUCCAAA